GCUCUGGGUUGUGGGAGUUGGGGAGCUGCUCCGGCUUCGGCGCGGAGGGGCGGCGGCCGGGGAGGCGGCGGCGGCGGCAGGUGAGAGGCCGGGGUCGGGCGGCCGGGCGGCGCGAGGUCCUAGACCCAGGACGACGCUGAGCCAGGCGUCCAGCUUCUGUGGCUCAGUUUACCCAGCUCUGAGAGUCUUGCCCCGAGGGAUCGGCGACCUCAAUCUGACAGUCGUGAUUUUGAGCUUGACAAGCAAGGGGAUUCCCCGCUCUGAGCCUCAGUUUUUCUAAGAAAUGGGGAUCACGAUAGUACUUAGCUCAUAGUACACCUGAAUCUUAGCGUAAGGUAAUCUACGUAAAGCCUUAAGCGGAGGAUAAUUUUGCGUUAUGUAUAAAAGUGUAAAUUGCACACACCUAUAGACCCUGCAAGCUCCUUUCUAGGACUCUGUCCUGCAGAAAUACUCAUUUAAGUGUGCAAAACGAGGCGUACUGGGUGUUUUCUGCAGCCUUGUUUAUAAUUGUGACACAUUGGAAACAGCCUAAAUGUCCAGCAAAGAGUUCUUUCUGCUCCAUGAUUUCAUGUAAUUUCUACCUUUAAUAGUAGUAGUUGUAAAAGCUGAAACGAAGAACAGAGCCAGUAAUAAGUAGCUCUCAGUAAUUGAAUGAUUAGUAGGUGCCAGACACCGCCAAGUGUUUCCCUUGCGUUAAUUUAACCUUCCUAACAUCCACCGAGGUAGGUACGGUUAUUUUCUCUCCAUAUAACGUGUGGGGAAACCGAGGUUCUUAGCCAUUUAAGUGAGUUAACUAAGAUGACAUCACUGGGGAGUGGAAGAGCUGGCAUUUGAACCCAGAUCUGUUGGAUGUGUCCAGUUGACUCCUGCAUUGCCUUUCUGGAUUCCCAGGAGCCAUGUUGUCAGAAGUCCUACUGGUGUCUGCUCCGGGGAAAGUCAUCCUUCAUGGAGAACAUGCCGUGGUACAUGGCAAGGUAGCACUGGCUGUAUCCUUGAACUUGAGAACAUUCCUCCGGCUUCAACCCCACAGCAAUGGGAAAGUGGACCUCAGCUUACCCAACAUUGGUAUCAAGCGGGCCUGGGAUGUGGCCAGGCUUCAGUCACUGGACACAAGCUUUCUGGAGCAAGGUGAUGUCACAACACCCACCUCAGAGCAAGUGGAGAAGCUAAAGGAGGUUGCAGGCUUGCCUGACGACUGUGCUGUCACCGAGCGCCUGGCUGUGCUGGCCUUUCUUUACUUAUACCUGUCCAUCUGCCGGAAGCAGAGGGCCCUGCCGAGCCUGGAUAUCGUAGUGUGGUCGGAGCUGCCCCCCGGGGCGGGCUUGGGCUCCAGCGCCGCCUACUCGGUGUGUCUGGCAGCAGCCCUCCUGACUGUGUGCGAGGAGAUCCCAAACCCGCUGAAGGACGGGGAUUGCGUCAACAGGUGGACCAAGGAGGAUUUGGAGCUAAUUAACAAGUGGGCCUUCCAAGGGGAGAGAAUGAUUCACGGGAACCCCUCCGGAGUGGACAAUGCUGUCAGCACCUGGGGAGGAGCCCUCCGAUACCAUCAAGGGAAGAUUUCAUCCUUAAAGAGGUCGCCAGCUCUCCAGAUCCUGCUGACCAACACCAAAGUCCCUCGCAAUACCAGGGCCCUUGUGGCUGGCGUCAGAAACAGGCUGCUCAAGUUCCCAGAGAUCGUGGCCCCCCUCCUGACCUCAAUAGAUGCCAUCUCCCUGGAGUGUGAGCGCGUGCUGGGAGAGAUGGGGGAAGCCCCAGCCCCGGAGCAGUACCUCGUGCUGGAAGAGCUCAUUGACAUGAACCAGCACCAUCUGAAUGCCCUCGGCGUGGGCCACGCCUCUCUGGACCAGCUCUGCCAGGUGACCAGGGCCCGCGGACUUCACAGCAAGCUGACUGGCGCAGGCGGUGGUGGCUGUGGCAUCACACUCCUCAAGCCAGGGCUGGAGCAGCCAGAAGUGGAGGCCACGAAGCAGGCCCUGACCAGCUGUGGCUUUGACUGCUUGGAAACCAGCAUCGGUGCCCCCGGCGUCUCCAUCCACUCAGCCACCUCCCUGGACAGCCGAGUCCAGCAAGCCCUGGAUGGCCUCUGAGAGGAGCCCACGACACUGCAGCCCCACCCAGAUGCCCCUUUCUGGAUUAUUCUGGGGGCUGCAGUUCGACUCUGUGCUGGCCAGCGAGCGCCCAGCUCCUGACACUGCUGGAGAGGCCCCAGCCGCUUGGCGAUGCCAGCCAAGCUCUGCAGUCCCAGCGGUGGGACCUAGGGAGGCAUGGUCUGCCCUCUGCAUCCUCUGGAGCCAGCCGAGCAGGAGGCCUAGGAGGGUCCUCUGAGACUCCAGACCUGAGGCGAGAAGGGCUGCUUCCCUGAAGCUCCCACAGUCCCAUCUGCUUCAGGCCCCCGCCUUGGCCUGUGUUCUUCCUGGCCGCCUGGGUCCAAUGCUCAGGUGCUGGGGCCUGGUUCCCGGAGAAGUGUGCCUUCUCUCUCCCUUUUCAGGGACCGCCCCCUGUCUCUCAGGGCCAGGCCUCUCCCUCCUCCAGGAAGCCUUCCCCUACCCCUUGUCGCCCCUCCCUCCCAGAGCACCUGCUGUCUGGGUGGCUCACUCAGCACUUGGUGUGGCCUUCCCUUCUACCUAGCGGGAUGGGGCUCCCCCAGGGGCUGUCCCGGAGGCGGUGGGCCUGGUUAAAUAAGGCAGGGUUUAUAUGCACUUUCUUCCGAUCUGUACCUGAGAGGUUUGUGGAAAAGAUGGCAAAUGGGGAAUAAAAAGAUUUUGUGUCAACAGUAGAGACUCCAGGCCACCAGCACCUCCCUCUGUCCCUGUCCCCUCUCCAGCUGUUUCCUCCAUGGAGCUCUUCAGCAAUGGAGGGAAAUAGGGUUUGGGGUCACUUUGUUGUGCGUCUUGGGGAUGAGGUGGCUUUUCCCAGAUGGCCCUUGCUGGAGAGGGACUGGGACACGGCUCUCAGUCCAUCAGCACAACUCUAGGCUGCUGCUGCGGAGGGAGAAGUUGAGCUUCCUAGCUCCAGAAUCACAAGCACCCACGAGAGCACAGACCUGUGUAAGACAGGAAAGCAGAACCUGCCAUCGCUCCUGGGGCGCGCCUUCCUUUCUGAAAUGAACUGGCUGGAUGGAGAAAACAGACUCAAAUGUUCUGGCCCGGGUGCCUGGCACUCCCCACCCCCGCCCCCCACCGGCCCUAUUUGAACUUUAUAUUGCAGUCAGCUUGGUGCUUUCCGAAAUGCCAUUAGCCAUCAGGAAACCCUUGUAGUUGGUGCCUUGCCAGCCAGAACCUCUGGGACCCACGGACCUGCAAAGAGGCCGAGUGGAAAGGUGGGGGCCGGCGCAGGGAUUUCAGGAUGAGGUGAAAGCGAUUCAGUGCGCGUCUGCCCUUGGCCACUAGGGGGCAGCUGGCGGCCUUCCCUGCUGUUGUCUUCCUGCAGGGUGAGAGGAGCAGGAGCCGAGCUCCACCCCCACGCCAGCCUUGGGCCCGGCCUGGGAUCACUGCUGGGAACGUGAGAGUGAAGGGAGGACGCCUACCCCAGCUUAACUUGUAGAAAUGGCCCCAGAUCACUGAUGGCUGUUCCCUGCCCCUUCCCUUCAAAACACAACGCAUAAAGCAGUAAUACUAAUUAAUACUGAACGCUCA